AUGGCUCGCUGGGAGGAAGGAUACCGCCACCCGUCACCACCCCCCGCCAGAAGCUCCUUCGUGACUCCUCUGCGCGUGCCUUCCCACACCUCCUCCGUCCGGGACUGCGAGGAGUGGGCGGUCGACUCGAGUUCGCAGCCCAGGCCUCCCACACGCCCCUCCCUGCCCUCCCCUGAGCCGGUGCUGCGCUCCUCUAAUUGGGACUCCGAGCCGGGGCUAUUUCUGGCGCUGGCGCGGCUCCAAGAAGGCAUCCGCAUUUGCUACCAGCGGCGGCCGCGGCGGAGCCAGGCCGGUCCUCAGCGCCCAGCACCGCCGCUCCCGGCAACCCGGAGCGCGCACCGCAGGCCGGCGGCCGAGCUCGCGCGCGCGCCGCCGGCUUUAUUCCCAGGCCGGGGCGGCGCGAGCCGGCGGCGGGGGAGGGCCGCGCGGCGCGGGGGCGGGCGGCGGGGCCCGGCGGCGCGGGGAGGACGCCCGCACCCCUUCCCCCGCGCCGCGGGCGCCCUGCGGGGGGCGGGGACCCGGGAAAGGCGCGCGGUGGGGGAGGGGGCGCGCAGCUGCGGCGAGCGCGAGUUGUGCACCCGGCGGAGCCCGGAGGAGCCCGGCGCACCUCGCGCGGCGGCCGCUCCCGCUGGAGCCGGAGCCCGAGCCCGAGCCCGGGCCCGGGUGAGGGGCGGGGAGAGACACGGGCUGCGGCGCGGCAGGAGAGUGGGGGGUCGGGCGCCCCCCGCAGCUCAGGGAAGUUCUGGAAGUGAGGGAGAUGGGGAGGAACCCCCAAAUUCGGCCCUACGCCCUCUCGGCCUUUCUCUCGCGCCCCCUCCGCAGAUGAGGCCGGAGCGCGGGCCUGGGUUUGGGGCUUCACCCCGACCCCACCUCUGGCCUGGCCCGCGCCUCUUCAGCCCCAGGGGCCGGGCCUGCCCUCCGCCCCCACAAACUGGUUUCGCUGCUUUGCUGGGCUCUGUUGGAACUAGUCCCUUUGACUCCCCGUUUCUAUUUUAUUUUCUUCUGGGGCUUUAUUUUGCGGGGAGGGGACGGAGGGAGGGGGCUUUCUUCCUCUCCCCCGCGCCCGCGCGCGCCAGGUUUCCUGCCCCAAGGCGGGCUUGGGUGCCCCCUCUGGCAGGAAGUGGGGCCGGGUGCACCCGCGUGGCGGUGCAUGCGGUCGGGGUGCGCUGCUUUCCCGCGCCUGCAGGAGCGGCCUGCGCCCCUCCCCCCGCGCGCCCUGGCCCCGGGUCCCGCCGGCCGGCCUGCAACGGCCGGGCGCAGACACUUGCAGAGUCACCCUCGGGCCGGGUCUGGAGCCUGAUGCCUCGGGGGUUUAGCCCUAGCCGCUAG